AAAAAAAAAAAAAAAAAAAAAAAAUUUGUCUUCAGAGACCACAGGCUGGAAAACUAGAUCUUGCCCUCAAAUGUGUCUUGUUUGGCUGCUGCCUUCUUCUUUUUUUUUUUUUUAAAUCAUUUUAAAAAUAGACGUAACAUAAAAUUUACCAUCUUAAGCAUAUAUAUAUAUUUUUUUUCUUGAGAGAGAAUCUUGCUCUGUCACCCAGGCUGGAGUGAAGUGGCAUGAUCUCGGCUCACUGCAACCUCUGCCUCCUGAGUUCAAGGAAUUCUCCCACUUCAGCCUCCUGAGUAGCUGGGACUACAGGUGCACACCACCACACCUGGCUAAUUUUUGUAUUUUUAGUAGAGAUGGGGUUUCACCAUGUUGGCCAGGCUGGUCUUAAAUUCCUGACCUCAGGUGAUCCACCUGCUUAAGCCUCCCAAAGUGCUGGGAUUAUUGGCGUGAGCCACCGCGCCCGGCUGAUCUGAAGCAUUUUUGAGAGUAACGUUCAGCAGCAGUACAUUCUCAUUGUGCAACAACCAUCACCAUCUGAUACAGUUUGGCUCUGUGUCCCCACCCAAAUUUCAUCUCGAAUUGUAAUCCCCACAUGUCAAGGGAGGGACCUGGUGAGAGGUGAACGGAUCAUGGGGUGGUUUCCUCCAUGCAGUUCUUGUGAUAGUGAGUUCUCAUGAGGUCUGAUGGUUUAAAAGUGGCAGUUUGCCCUUCAUGUGCUCACUAUCUCUCUCCUGCCGCCAUAGAAGACAUGCUUUGUGUCUCCUCCUCCUUCUGCCAGGAUUGUAAGUUUCCUGAGGCCUCCCCAGCCAUGUGGAACUGUGAGUCAAUUAAACCUCUUUUAUUUAUCUAUCUAUUUAUUUAUUUAUUUAUUUAUUUUUAUUUUUUGAGAUGGAGUCUCUGUCUCCCAGGCUGGAGUACAGUGGCACAAUCUCAGCUCACUGCAACUUUCGCCUCCUGGGUUCAAGUGAUUCUCCUGUCUCCGGCUCCCGCAUAGCUGGGACUACAGGUGUACACCACCACACCCGGCUUUUGUAUUUUUAGUAGAGACAGGGUUUCACCAUGUUGGCCAGGCUGGUCUCAGACUCCUGACCUCAAGUGAUCCACCUGCCUCGGCCUCCCAAAGUGCUGGGAUUACCGGUGUGAGUCACCAUGCCUGAUGAAACCUCUUUUCUUUAUAAAUUACCCAGUCUCAGGUAUUUCUUUAUAGCAGUGUGAAAACUGACUAAUACACCAUCCAUCUCCAGAACUCUUUUCAUCUUCUGCUACUGAAAUUUGGGCCUCAUUAAAGAGUAACUCCUCAUUCGCCAUCUGUCUCCGUGGGUUUGACUGCUCAUGUACUUACUGAACACCUACUGUGUACCAGGCACUGUUCCAGGCACUGGGAGUACAGUGCUGAACACAACAGACAAAAAUCCCUGCCUUCGCAUAUAUCAUCUCGUUUAAUCCUCGAGACAGCUUCCAUGAGGUAGAACACCUGAAGGAGAAGCUCAUUAGCCAGGCCCAGGAAGUGAGCCGACUGCGAUCUGAGCUGGGGGGCACCGACUUGGAGAAGCACCGGGACCUGCUGAUGGUGGAGAAUGAGCGACUGAGGCAGGAGAUGCGGCGCUGUGAGGCCGAGCUGCAAGAGCUGCGCACAAAGCCAGCAGGUCCCUGCCCAGGUUGUGAGCACAGCCAGGAGAGCGCCCAGCUCCGUGACAAGCUGUCCCAGCUGCAGCUGGAGAUGGCGGAAAGCAAAGGCAUGCUGUCAGAGCUGAACCUAGAGGUGCAGCAGAAGACCGACCGGCUGGCUGAGGUGGAGCUGCGACUCAAGGACUGCCUGGCUGAGAAGGCACAGGAGGAGGAGCGGCUUAGUCGGCGCCUGCGUGACAGCCACGAGACCAUUGCCAGCCUGCGGGCCCAGUCCCCACCUGUCAAGUAUGUCAUCAAGACAGUGGAGGUGGAGUCGUCCAAGACCAAGCAGGCCCUCAGCGAGUCCCAGGCCCGGAACCAGCACCUGCAGGAGCAGGUGGCUAUGCAGAGGCAGGUGCUGAAGGAGAUGGAACAGCAGCUGCAGAGCUCACACCAGCUGACCGCGCGGCUCCGGGCGCAGAUUGCCAUGUACGAGUCAGAGCUGGAGCGGGCCCAUGGGCAGAUGCUGGAGGAGAUGCAGUCCCUGGAAGAGGACAAGAACCGGGCCAUUGAGGAGGCCUUUGCCAGAGCCCAGGUGGAGAUGAAGGCUGUGCACGAGAAUCUAGCAGGCGUCCGGACCAACUUGCUGACCUUGCAGCCGGCACUGCGGACCCUCACCAACGACUACAAUGGGCUCAAGCGGCAGGUGCGCGGCUUCCCACUGCUGCUGCAGGAGGCCCUCAGGAGUGUCAAGGCCGAGAUAGGCCAGGCCAUCGAGGAGGUCAACAGCAACAACCAGGAGCUGCUGCGCAAGUACCGCCGCGAGCUGCAGCUGCGUAAGAAGUGCCACAAUGAGCUCGUGCGGCUGAAAGGGAACAUCCGAGUGAUUGCUCGUGUCCGGCCAGUCACCAAAGAGGAUGGGGAAGGACCUGAGGCCACCAAUGCUGUGACUUUCGAUGCCGACGACGACUCCAUCAUCCACCUGCUGCACAAGGGCAAGCCUGUGUCCUUCGAGCUGGACAAGGUCUUCUCCCCACAGGCCUCGCAGCAGGACGUGUUCCAGGAGGUGCAGGCCCUGGUCACCUCUUGCAUUGAUGGCUUCAAUGUCUGCAUCUUUGCGUACGGCCAGACGGGCGCCGGCAAGACGUACACGAUGGAGGGGACCGCUGAGAACCCAGGUAUCAACCAGCGGGCCCUGCAGCUGCUCUUCUCCGAGGUGCAGGAGAAGGCGUCUGACUGGGAGUACACCAUCACCGUCAGCGCUGCGGAGAUCUACAAUGAGGUCCUCAGGGACCUGCUAGGGAAAGAGCCUCAGGAAAAACUGGAGAUCCGGCUGUGCCCAGACGGCAGUGGGCAGCUGUAUGUACCAGGGCUGACUGAGUUCCAAGUGCAGAGCGUGGACGACAUCAACAAGGUGUUUGAGUUUGGCCACACUAAUCGCACGACCGAGUUCACCAACCUGAACGAGCACAGCUCCCGCUCGCACGCGCUGCUCAUCGUGACGGUGCGAGGCGUGGACUGCAGCACAGGCCUCCGCACCACGGGGAAGCUGAACCUGGUGGACUUGGCUGGCUCGGAGCGCGUGGGCAAGUCGGGGGCCGAGGGCAGCCGCCUGCGGGAGGCGCAGCACAUCAACAAGUCGCUGUCGGCUCUGGGGGACGUCAUUGCUGCCCUGCGCUCCCGCCAGGGCCACGUGCCCUUCCGCAACUCCAAGCUCACCUACCUGCUGCAGGAUUCGCUUAGUGGUGACAGCAAGACCCUCAUGGUGGUACAGGUGUCCCCCGUGGAGAAGAACACUAGCGAGACGCUCUAUUCCCUCAAGUUUGCUGAGAGGGUGCGCUCUGUGGAGCUGGGGCCUGGGCUACGCAGGGCAGAGCUUGGGUCCUGGUCAAGCCAGGAGCAUCUAGAGUGGGAGCCGGCUUGUCAGACGCCACAGCCCUCGGCACGGGCCCACUCAGCCCCCAGCUCUGGGACCAGUAGCCGCCCUGGAUCCAUCCGGAGGAAGCUGCAGCCCUCGGGGAAGUCGCGGCCACUGCCUGUGUGACGGAUGUGACCCCGCUGGGCCUGAAGCUGGGCCCUCACUGGCCUGUCCCUGCUGCAGCGCCAGGACCCCCGGAGGUAGAGGCGAGAGUGGAGGCUCUUCUUCUGCCCCGUCUCCCCUCAAAGAUGAGAAACAUGUUCAGAAGGAAACGGUGUCUCUCGGCUGUGGCUCUGAGUGCAAAUUGCAUGGGCGGAAAGGCGGGGGUGGCUGCUCUUCCUGGCAGGCCUGGGCCAUCAGCGAACUGGGCCCCGUGAGGAGGGCGGGAGUGUGGAGGAGGGUGGGCCUCUCACCCAGGCUUUCUCGGCCCCUCUCCUCAGCUUGCAGAGCUGGCCAGCCCCCUCCUUAGGGGGUGGGCGAGGAGCCUCUGGGCAGACCCAAGAACCAUGGGGACUGGGGUGGGUUGGUGGCACCAAUGGCAGCCCUCCCCGCCCCUCUCCUUCAAGGAGGGUUCCCGCAGCUGGGGGGUGUGCGGAGGCGCAUGGCCUCCCGCCACGGGGCCGUGCUGUGUUUAUGGCUGGCAGAGGCAGCCAGCGGGUGGGGGAUUCUGCUGCUCGCUCACCUGCCUGGCUCGCUGGUCUCUCGAAUUUUCUUCCCUCUGAAAUCCUAUUUAAGAACUUUUGGAAGCUUAGCCAUUUUUACUUAUUAAAAUAAAAGAAGCCUUUUUACACAA